UAUAAUUAAUGUAUAUACAAUAUAUUGUAUUUCUAUAAUUUUGUUUAUAUGCUACAGUAGUGUACAAAUAAGAACUAUAUUCCAAUAAACUGGCCUUUUAGAACUCAAAAACAUAAUAGAGAGCAGAAGUGUAACUAGCCUUUUAUAUCUGACAAAACUGUGAGAGAAUAGAUUUGAGAAGAUCUGAAAAACUGACUUUUUUAGAACCAAUUAGGUGUUCAGAACAUAAGGAUGAAGUGAAAGCCUAGUUAGACAAAUGAUACUGGUGCCAAACAGCAGGGUCUUAUUUUCAUAAUAAUUAUAUACUAGAGGAAAGAAGGGCACUUCUAGGUCUUCACAGCUAAAUCAAAUAAUUGGAAUGAAUAUAUUGAUCUAACAUCACUUUGAAAAGGUUGUUAAAAACAUGCUCAAAUUUUUUUCCUAUUUAGAUUUACAAAGAUUUUGUUCAACACGAAGGGUCAAUAUGUAAUAUAGAAUGUAAUUAAAGUAACAGCCAACUGUUAGGUACAGUACUAACUGCUUCAUAUGGUUUAAUUUAAUAAUUUAUGACUACUUUCCAAGGUGGUGACUGUUGUGAUACCAGUCAUACAGAUGAGGACACUGAGGCUUAGAAAGAGUAAAUGUUUUUCCCACCCUCAGCCUUAGCAACUUUAAACCCAGGCUGUGUGACUUGAGAUUUCGUGGGGUUUUUUGUUUAUUUCGCUUUGUUUUUGAGACAAAGUCUUGCCCUGUCACUCAGGCUGGUGUGCAGUGGCAUGAUCUUGGCUCACUGCAACCUCUGUCUCCAGGGUUCAGGCAAUUCUCCUGCUUCAGCCUCCUGAGUAUCUGGGACUACAGGCACGUGCCACCACGUCCGGCUAAUUUUUGUAUUUUUGGUAGAGACGGGGUUUCACCAUGCUGGCAGGGCUGGUCUUGAACUCCUGACCUCAAGUGAUCCAUCAGCCUCAGCCUCCCAAAGUGCUGGGAUUACAGGCAUGAGCUACCAUGCCCAGUGAGAUUUCGCAUUUUAAACUACUGACCAUUUCUUUAAAAACUGAGUAGAGUUCUUAGUGACUGUAAGUCUGGUAGAAUGCAGCAGCUUCCAGAUCCAUUGUAUUUUCUUCCUACUGAUAACACUUGCCUUUUAACAAUACCUUCCACUGAGAUAAUGGCAAAAUUUUUUGGCUGGGAAGGAUGGCUGUUUAUGUGAAGUAGCAUACUAUCAGAAAAUGUUGUUUUAGCCAAAAAUGCGGGAUAAUAAACCUCUCAAAGAGCUCAGUUUCUUGUUUCUUCCAUACUGUAAUUCACAUUCUCAGAAGAUGACCCUUUUGUUCAAAUUGCAAUGGAUAAUUUUAGAAAUACUUUAUAUAUGUGAUCUGGAAAAGGGAUGAUACAGAUUUAUGACUUGGGCCAAGAUGGACAAGGAAUGAGCAGAGUUGCUGCUGUUUCACAGAAUUCUUUUGUUCUUGCUGAUGGAAACGUUGCUAGAACCAUGAAUCAUUCUUUCGAUCAGGGGGUGGUAAACUAAUGGCUGCUGUGGGUAAAUUGUGCAGGAGAUCUGUUUUUGGAAGGCCAUUAAGCUAAGCAUUGUUAUUGCAUUUUUAAAGAAUUGUUUUUAAAAAAUAAGAACAUGCAAUGGAGAUAGUAUAUUAUUCUUAAAGCCUCAAAUAUUUACCAUAUGAUGGUUACAAAUGUUUGCUGACUUGCACUCUAAAUAAUAUAACAUGAUAUUUUAAAAAAAGGAUACCUUUGGCUAAUUCAAAUUUUAACUAUGAAAAAGAGUUAAAAUGGAUGGACAGUUAGCCAAAGAUUGUUGUUCCCAUAGCAAGCAACUCAACUGAGAACGGAGGUGGAAGGGACAUAAGUUUGAAAAAGCUCUGACUAGCCUCCUGGUUUAGCCAGUAGAGGUGUGAAUCUCAAUGGGAUGGCAUCAGGAUUUGCAUCCAUAGGGCCCAUUCUUGCAUCUUAUUGGAGGAGAGAAAAUGUUUUGUUCAUCAAAAAGGGAUGAGAGCUAGGCAUGGUGGCUCAUACAUGUAAUCCUAGCUACUUGAGAGGCUGAGGCAGGAGGAUCACUUGAGGCCAGGAGUUCCAGACUAGCCUGGGCAGCAUAGAGAGAUGCUGUAUCUAAAAAAAUAAAAUAAAAAUUAGGUGUGAUGUAACGCACCUAUAGUCUCAGCUGCUCUGGAGGCUGAGGUCGGAGGAUCGUUUGAGCCCAGGAAUUUGAGGCUGCAAUGAGCUGUGACUGUGCCCCCUAGCCUUGGUAACAGAACGAGAUCCCCCUGCCCCCUUAAAAAACAAACAAAAACAAAACCAGGGUGGAUGAGUUUAAAAAGUUUUGAGCACUACUGAUACAUGGGCAUUCUUGGGGAAAUUUAAAAAAUAGUAACAAAUUUGGUAUUAACUCUUUAAUCUGUUUUUACUUUCUAAUUUUAAAUUAAGGGUUUAGAGCAGUAUAAUCUUAUAAAUAUUGUAGUUUUAUCUUCUACUUUUACCCUUAGAAUUUUUUAAAGUGUUCCCUUUUACCUAUAGGAAUUUAUGCUUUUAUGCUAGUUUCCUUAGUAGUGCAAGUGAACUGUGAAAUGUUUCUCUUUUUCUGGCUCAGUUUAAUGUCUGUUGAAAACUAUUCAAAAUGUCUGUUGUAUGACUUGCUUAUAUCUUGCACAUUGAUAUAUACACAUAUUUGAGGUAAUAGGUCAUUUGUGUGAUAGUAUGAAUUGUAGGGUCCAGAGUUAGAUUGCUAUGGUUUGACUCUCUUAUGUGCUGUGUUUGAACUUGGGAAGGUCUCAAUAUCUUUUUAAAUAAAUUCUAUAAUUUUUUUAUAGAAUGGGAAUAAUGAUAGUAUAUACCUCUCAGAGUUAUGAGUAGUUCCAUGUAAAACUUACCACACUUACCAUAGGGCCUGGCAUUCAGUGUGCAGCCAAUAUGUGUUAGCUAUAUUAGUAUAAUUUAUCACACUGACUUUAUAAUCUGGUCAUACUUUUUAUGUCUUGAAUGUUAAGAAUUUGAAAGCACUUAGGGUCACAGAAAGUAACUCGUAUAUCAGAAAUUGGGGAUCUUGAGGGGUUAUUUUUCCCCUGAAAUAAUAUUGUAUGGCAGAUUACUGAGAAACCACAUAUAUACAAUAUAGUAAGAGAUUUUAUUAUUAUAUUAUUUUAAAUGUGUCUUUUAAUUAUUUACCAGUGAAAUAAAAGCUAAUUUAAAUUAAAAGCUUAAGUUUAUAUUAAAGAUAUGGGGUUCUUACUAAGUUGAAAACUGAAAAUCACAUAUGUAUAUCUGUAAAUAAUGGAUUAAUAUUUAUGAAGAAUAUGAAUAUGAUUAAUAUGUUUAUAAAGAAUGUUUAGAAAAAGUAGAAAAGAUUGUUUUAUUUUAAAAAAUAUUUUUGUUUAUUCUGUGUGUGUGUGUGUGUGUGUGUGUGUGUGUGUGUGUGUGUGGUAUAGUUAAGAGCAAAAAGAUUCAUGGCCCCUGCUCUUUUGUAGUUAAUGGUGAAGUAGAAAAACAUUAAAUUACACUUUUAAAUGUAUAAUCACAAGCCAAUAUAUUGAGUUAAUAAAGGAAAGUCACAGGAAGUGUGCAACCAAGAAAACAGACUUGGAUUGUGUAGAGUAUAGAAAAACAAAGGAAGUUACAUUAGAGGGAAGAUCUGAGACACAUGGAAGAGUUGUCUGGGCAAGGAAGUGUGGGGAAAUGCAGAGUGUAUGCUAUAUGAUAAAGUCUGACAGGAGAGAGAGAUUAUGCGUAAAUAACCUGAAAGAAGGCCAUGUGUUUGAAACGUGAAAAGUGAGAGUUGGGGAAAGGGACUGGGAAUGUGCCAGGUGAAGCUAGAAAAAUAAGAAGUGACCAUACAUGCAUUUCUGGGCUGAUAGACCAAGUUAAGGAUUUGGAUCUUUAUCCAAAGAGUGAGGAAAGCAUCAGAAGUGUUUUAAGUAGGGGUGACUUGAUCCAAUAUGUAUUUUGGAAAGAACAUUCUAAUUGCAGUAUAGAGAAUAGAUUUGAAUGGGGCAUGAGUGCAUAUGGGAAAGGUAUGCAUUUAUUGCAAAGAUUAUUUGGACUGUUAUGGAGAUACAGGUAGAUGGAUUUAAAAAUAGGAAGGAAAAAUUAAGUUGAACUUGGUGACUGCUUGGAUAUUGGGAAUAUGAUGGGAAGGAGGAAGGAAUGAACUGUGUGCAAAAUGCAGCUCCUUGGUUUCUGGCUUCCAAGGUUGGAUAAAUGGGGUUGACAUCCACCCAGGUAGGGAACACUUUAGUGGGGAAUGUUUUCAUGAGGAUCCAUCAAUUCAGUUUUGCAUAUGUUGAGUUUCAGAUGCUUUGGGGCUCUAGAGAGCUGUUUUAAGAAAGUUUGCUAUGCAAGUCUAUGCUAUAAAUAGAAAUUUGGCAAUCAUUGUUAUAACAAUUGUCCAAAGAGAGAGUAUAUAGUGAGAAGAAAAGAGGAUCUGGAACUGGACUCUGGUACCUAGGAUCUUAAGGAACUUCACUAUUUAAUGGCUAUAUAGAGGAGUAUAAGCCUAAAAGAAAAAUGAGAAGGAAUGGUUGGAGAGGAAGAAAGCAAGCCAAGGAGUGUCACAAAAGUUAAGAGAAGAUAGUUUGCAAAUGAGGAAGUGUUCAACAGUUAGGUGAAAUAUUAUGGGACAUUAAAUAAGGUAUAGAUUUAAAAAUGCUUAUUGGAGUUAUUGAUAAUUGAAGGUGAACUUUUGAUAAGAGCUAUUUUUUGUAAAGUCAUGAGUGUGGGAGCUAGUGUGGAGUAGAUUGAGGAGAGGAUGGGAUACGAAAUUAGAUGGACUAUGGACCAUUCUUUUAAAAACAUGUUUCCGGAGAGGAAGAGAACGGGAAAGGGGUAGCCAGGAUAUUUGGGUGGGGAGGUGUUGGAUAAUAGCAGUUAGGCAGGAUUUUUGUUUUUUCCUAAAGUGGAUGCAAAAUGAGCAUGUUUACAUGUAGAUGGGAAGGAGUUGGUUGAGAGGAAGUUAGUGUACAUACUAGAAUGUGGAGGUCUAAUUUAUAGUGUAGGAUUUCCGUGCAGUCAGAGAAGUUAGGAUUCAAAGCAUAAGUAGAGGGAUUGGAUCUUAAAUAUUUAUUAAGAGGGACAGUUGUGUUAAUAAGAGACAGAAUUGGUACAGGUGUAGAUAGGUUUACAGAUUUGAUAGGGAAGAAACAAAGCUUCAGCUUUAAAAAAGGUUCUCCUGUAAAGUAGGUUAGGUCAUCUGCUGAGAAAAUGAGGGGUGGGGAAGAGGAUUCUUGGGAAAGAGAGGAUAAUAGCAUUGUUUGUUAGUCUGUUUCCACUGUUCUUUCCAGAGACCCUUUCAUGGUGGUACCUCAGGGACUGCUAAGAGGAAGCAAGUAGAGAGUCAAGCAUUGAGAUAUGUGUUCCCUGAUGCCACUUAAGUGAAGUAUUACAGACACUUAGCACCUGAUCACUUGCUGCAAAUAUGUCAUCGACUAGGACCUCUUCUUGAACAAGAAAUUCCUCAAAGUGUUCCUGGAGUACAAACUUUAUUAGGAGCUGGAAGACAGUCUUUACUACGCACAAAUAAAAGCUGCAAGCAUGUUGUGUGGAAAGGAUCUGCUCUGGCUGCGUUGCACUGUGGAAGACCACCUGAGUCACCAGUUAACUAUGGUAGCCCACCCAGCAUUGCGGAUACUCUGUUUUCAAGGAAGCUGAAUGGGAAAUACAGACUUGAGCGACUUGUUCCAACUGCAGUGUAUCAGCACAUGAAAAUGCAUAAACGAAUUCUUGGACACUUGUCAUCUGUGUACUGUGUAACUUUUGAUCGAACUGGCAGACGGAUAUUUACUGGUUCUGAUGACUGUCUUGUGAAAAUAUGGGCAACAGAUGAUGGGAGGUUGUUAGCUACCUUAAGAGGACAUGCUGCUGAAAUAUCAGACAUGGCUGUAAACUAUGAGAAUACCAUGAUAGCAGCUGGAAGUUGUGAUAAAAUGAUCCGAGUCUGGUGUCUUCGAACCUGUGCACCUUUGGCUGUUCUUCAGGGCCAUAGUGCAUCUAUUACAUCACUACAGUUCUCACCAUUGUGCAGUGGCUCAAAGAGAUAUCUAUCUUCUACUGGGGCAGAUGGCACUAUUUGUUUUUGGCUCUGGGAUGCUGGAACCCUUAAAAUAAACCCAAGACCUGCAAAAUUUACAGAGCGCCCUCGGCCUGGAGUUCAAAUGAUCUGUUCUUCUUUUAGUGCUGGUGGAAUGUUUCUGGCGACGGGAAGCACAGAUCAUAUUAUUCGGGUUUAUUUUUUUGGAUCAGGUCAGCCAGAGAAAAUAUCAGAAUUGGAGUUUCAUACUGACAAAGUUGACAGUAUCCAGUUUUCCAACACUAGUAACAGGUUUGUAAGUGGCAGUCGUGAUGGGACAGCACGUAUUUGGCAAUUUAAACGAAGAGAGUGGAAGAGCAUUUUGUUGGAUAUGGCUACUCGUCCAGCAGGCCAAAACCUUCAAGGAAUAGAAGAUAAAAUCACAAAAAUGAAGGUUACUAUGGUAGCUUGGGAUCGACAUGACAAUACAGUUAUAACUGCAGUUAAUAACAUGACUCUGAAAGUUUGGAAUUCUUACACUGGUCAACUAAUUCAUGUCCUGAUGGGUCAUGAAGAUGAGGUAUUUGUUCUUGAACCACACCCGUUCGAUCCUAGAGUUCUCUUUUCUGCUGGUCAUGAUGGAAACGUGAUAGUGUGGGAUCUGGCAAGAGGAGUCAAAAUACGAUCUUAUUUCAAUAUGAUUGAAGGCCAAGGACAUGGCGCAGUAUUUGACUGCAAAUGCUCUCCUGAUGGUCAGCAUUUUGCAUGCACAGACUCUCAUGGACAUCUUUUAAUUUUUGGCUUUGGGUCCAGUAGCAAAUAUGACAAGAUAGCAGAUCAGAUGUUCUUUCAUAGUGAUUAUCGGCCACUUAUUCGUGAUGCCAACAAUUUUGUAUUAGAUGAACAGACUCAGCAAGCACCUCAUCUUAUGCCUCCCCCUUUUUUGGUUGAUGUUGAUGGUAACCCUCAUCCAUCAAGAUAUCAAAGAUUAGUUCCUGGCCGUGAAAAUUGCAGGGAGGAGCAACUCAUCCCUCAGAUGGGAGUAACUUCCUCAGGACUGAAUCAAGUUUUAAGUCAGCAAGCAAACCAGGAGAUCAGCCCACUGGACAGCAUGAUUCAAAGACUACAACAGGAGCAAGACCUGAGACGUUCUGGUGAAGCAGUUAUCAGUAAUACCAGCCGUUUAAGUAGAGGCUCCAUAAGUUCUACCUCAGAGGUUCAUUCACCACCAAACGUAGGACUAAGACGUAGUGGACAAAUUGAAGGUGUACGGCAAAUGCACAGCAACGCACCAAGAAGUGAAAUAGCCACAGAGCGGGAUCUGGUAGCUUGGAGUCGAAGGGUGGUAGUACCCGAGCUAUCAGCUGGUGUAGCCAGUAGGCAAGAAGAAUGGAGAACUGCAAAGGGAGAAGAAGAAAUAAAGACUUACAGGUCAGAAGAGAAAAGAAAACACUUAACUGUUCCAAAAGAGAAUAAAAUACCCACUGUCUCAAAGAAUCAUGCUCAUGAGCAUUUCCUGGAUCUUGGAGAAUCCAAAAAGCAACAGACAAAUCAACACAAUUAUCGUACAAGAUCUGCAUUGGAAGAGACUCCUAGACCCUCAGAAGAGAUAGAAAAUGGCAGUAGUUCUUCAGAUGAAGGCGAAGUAGUUGCUGUCAGUGGUGGAACAUCCGAAGAAGAAGAGAGAGCAUGGCACAGUGAUGGCAGUUCUAGUGACUACUCCAGUGAUUACUCUGACUGGACAGCAGAUGCAGGAAUUAAUCUGCAGCCACCAAAGAAAGUUCCUAAGAAUAAAACCAAGAAAGCAGAAAGCAGUUCAGAUGAAGAAGAAGAAUCUGAAAAACAGAAGCAAAAACAGAUUAAAAAGGAAAAGAAAAAAGUAAAUGAAGAAAAAGAUGGACCAAUAUCACCAAAGAAAAAGAAGCCCAAAGAAAGAAAACAAAAGAGAUUGGCUGUGGGAGAACUAACUGAAAAUGGUUUGACAUUAGAAGAAUGGUUGCCAUCAACAUGGAUUACAGAUACCAUUCCCCGAAGAUGUCCAUUUGUGCCACAGAUGGGUGAUGAGGUUUAUUAUUUCCGACAAGGACAUGAAGCCUAUGUCGAAAUGGCCCGGAAAAAUAAAAUAUAUAGUAUCAAUCCCAAAAAACAACCAUGGCAUAAAAUGGAGCUACGGGAACAAGAACUUAUGAAAAUAGUUGGCAUAAAGUAUGAAGUGGGAUUACCUACCCUUUGCUGCCUUAAACUUGCUUUUCUAGAUCCUGAUACUGGUAAACUGACUGGCGGAUCAUUUACCAUGAAAUACCAUGAUAUGCCUGACGUUAUAGAUUUCCUAGUCUUGAGACAACAAUUUGAUGAUGCAAAAUACAGGCGAUGGAAUAUAGGUGACCGCUUCAGGUCUGUCAUAGAUGAUGCCUGGUGGUUUGGAACAAUCGAAAGCCAGGAACCUCUUCAACUUGAGUACCCUGAUAGUCUGUUUCAAUGCUACAAUGUUUGCUGGGACAAUGGAGAUACAGAAAAGAUGAGUCCUUGGGAUAUGGAGCUUAUACCUAAUAAUGCUGUAUUUCCUGAAGAACUAGGUACCAGUGUUCCUUUAACUGAUGGUGAGUGCAGAUCACUAAUCUAUAAACCUCUUGAUGGAGAAUGGGGUACCAAUCCCAGGGAUGAAGAAUGUGAAAGAAUUGUGGCAGGAAUAAACCAGUUGAUGACACUAGAUAUUGCCUCAGCAUUUGUGGCCCCCGUGGAUCUGCAAGCCUAUCCCAUGUAUUGCACAGUAGUGGCAUAUCCAACGGAUCUAAGUACAAUUAAACAAAGACUGGAAAACAGGUUUUACAGGCGGGUUUCUUCCCUAAUGUGGGAAGUUCGAUAUAUAGAGCAUAAUACACGAACAUUUAAUGAGCCUGGAAGCCCUAUUGUGAAAUCUGCUAAAUUCGUGACUGAUCUUCUUCUACAUUUUAUAAAGGAUCAGACUUGUUAUAACAUAAUUCCACUUUAUAAUUCAAUGAAGAAGAAAGUUUUGUCUGAUUCUGAGGAUGAAGAGAAAGAUGCUGAUGUGCCAGGAACUUCUACUCGAAAAAGGAAGGACCAUCAGCCUAGAAGAAGAUUACGUAAUAGAGCCCAGUCUUACGAUAUUCAAGCAUGGAAGAAACAGUGUGAAGAAUUGUUAAAUCUCAUAUUUCAAUGUGAAGAUUCAGAGCCUUUCCGUCAGCCGGUAGAUCUCCUUGAAUAUCCAGACUACAGAGACAUCAUUGACACUCCAAUGGAUUUUGCUACCGUUAGAGAAACUUUAGAGGCUGGGAAUUAUGAGUCACCAAUGGAGUUAUGUAAAGAUGUCAGACUUAUUUUCAGUAAUUCCAAAGCAUAUACACCAAGCAAAAGAUCAAGGAUUUACAGCAUGAGUUUGCGCCUGUCUGCUUUCUUUGAAGAACACAUUAGUUCAGUUUUAUCAGAUUAUAAAUCUGCUCUUCGUUUUCAUAAAAGAAAUACCAUAACCAAAAGGAGGAAGAAAAGAAACAGAAGCAGCUCUGUUUCCAGUAGUGCUGCAUCAAGCCCUGAAAGGAAAAAAAGGAUCUUAAAACCCCAGCUAAAAUCAGAAAGCUCUACCUCUGCAUUCUCUACACCUACACGAUCAAUACCGCCAAGACACAAUGCUGCUCAGAUAAACGGUAAAACAGAAUCUAGUUCUGUGGUUCGAACCAGAAGCAACCGAGUGGUUGUAGAUCCAGUUGUCACUGAGCAACCAUCUACUUCUUCAGCUGCAAAGACUUUUAUUACAAAAGCUAAUGCAUCUGCAAUACCAGGGAAAACAAUACUAGAGAAUUCUGUGAAACAUUCCAAAGCUUUGAAUACUCUUUCCAGUCCUGGUCAAUCCAGUUUUAGUCAUGGCACUAGGAAUAAUUCUGCAAAAGAAAACAUGGAAAAGGAAAAGCCAGUCAAACGUAAAAUGAAGUCAUCUGUACUCCCAAAGGCGUCCACUCUUUCAAAGUCAUCAGCUGUCAUUGAGCAAGGAGAUUGUAAGAACAACGCUCUUGUACCAGGAACCAUUCAAGUAAAUGGCCAUGGAGGACAGCCAUCAAAACUUGUGAAGAGGGGACCUGGAAGGAAACCUAAAGUAGAAGUUAAUACCAAUAGUGGUGAAAUUAUACACAAGAAAAGGGGUAGAAAGCCCAAAAAGCUACAGUAUGCAAAGCCAGAAGAUUUAGAGCAAAAUAAUGUGCAUCCCAUCAGAGAUGAAGUACUUCCUUCUUCAACAUGCAAUUUUCUUUCUGAAACUAAUAAUGUAAAGGAAGAUUUGUUACAGAAAAAGAAUCGUGGAGGUAGGAAGCCCAAAAGGAAGAUGAAGACACAAAAAUUAGAUGCAGAUCUCCUAGUCCCUGCAAGUGUCAAAGUGUUAAGGAGAAGUAACCGAAAAAAGAUAGAUGAUCCUAUAGAUGAGGAAGAAGAGUUUGAAGAACUCAAAGGCUCUGAACCCCACAUGAGAACUAGAAAUCAAGGUCGAAGGACAGCUUUCUAUAAUGAGGAUGACUCUGAAGAGGAGCAAAGGCAGCUGUUGUUCGAAGACACCUCUUUAACUUUUGGAACUUCUAGUAGAGGACGAGUCCGAAAGUUGACUGAAAAAGCAAAAGCUAAUUUAAUUGGUUGGUAACUUGUACCAAAAUAUUUUACUUCAAAAUCUAUAAAGCAGGUACAGUUAAGGAAUAAGUAGAACUAAGGCUUCUGCUUCCUUGCUGCUGUGGUGGAGUAGGGAAUGUUAUGAUUUGAUUUGCAAAAAAAAAAAAAAAAAAAAAAACAAACUUACGAGACACUUCACUUCUUUAAAUGAAUAUAUAUAUAUAUAUAUAAAUAUAUACAUAUAUAUUUUAAAUGUUUGCUAUUUAUUGCCCUUAGAUAGGUUAUGCAUUUUCACAUUCAUUUCAUUCACUGUUUGAAACGAAAGAAAUUGAUCUAUAAUGAAUUCCUGAUUUAUUUAUAGAAAAGACAAUUCUGCUACACUCUUUAGGAGCAUAAUAUUCCUAGUGAUAGAGCAUUUCAUGUUAAAAUGAAUUAUUUUUGACCAAGUGAGGUACAUUUCUAUUGAUACAAGUCAUGCCCCUAAAAGAUAGAUGUUAUACAGAGUAGCAGUGAAUUAAGAAAUGUUUCCUCUAAAAGAUAAAUAUAAAAUUUCCACCAUUUGAUACCCUAAACAGUUUAAUUUUAAUUAUAGAAUGUUCAUCUACAAAGUAUCUAGAGGAGGCUUUUGCUUUAUUCCAUUUCUGCCAAACAAGAGAAAAUGUACUGAUGAAGGGAAACAUAUCCACAUUGGAAAACAUUUGACUGUCUAAUUUUUCAGACCUUGAUUCUUAUAUCACUCAAUCUCUGUUUAUUGUGCCAAAGACUGAGAAUCAGUGCAGUGGAAAGCCUGUUUUUGACGUCAGGACAGCAUACACUUUUCAAUAUUGGAAAGGCUAUAUAUUCUAAAGAGCAAGUUAUUAAAGAGUUAUGCUGAGAUAUAUCUUUUUUUGGUACUAAUAGAAAAUAAUGCACUGGUGGGUCCUUUGACAGAGAUGUUCUAGAGGAAAUGUUUAAGUGGUUAAAGGAUUCAAGGAAAAUACAGGAAAAAAGGUAUGGGAUUUGAUGUUUACUUGUUGAUCUGGAUUAAUGUCAUUUCUAAACUUUAGACAUAUCUAAUAGCCUAAAAUGACUUACAAAGAAACGUGUCUGUGUGUGUAUGUGUAUAUAUUGAUAAAUGGGUAUAAUUAAAUAUAUAUACAAACACAUACUUAUAUACUAUUACCCAGGUAUAAAUUCUUUUUUCAGGAUUUUUUAGAUAGCAGUAGAAUAAAAAUAAUUUUAAAAUGUCAUACUUUAUAGUUUAAUUUUAAGGGGGAAAUUGGUUAUUUUCAAUUAUUAAAGGUUAAAAUAGGCCAAAUCACUUUUUAUGCAAUCAUGUUUUAUACAGUGGUCUCAUUGCACAUUGUGUUUUUUCUGCACUUUUUACGGUAUCCUUAUCAUGCUGGUAUGUCAAUAUACACCCUAAAGAAAAACUCCAUUUAAUGAUUGUGCCUUGUAUUCUAUUAUUUUUUGCAUCAUUAGUAAAAUUAAGUUGUCUAUUGUAAAUGAUAACUAUAUGACUUAGGAGAAUGUAUUGCUAUAUGUACUGCUAUGGAAAAGGAAAGCAGUUAUUUAUUUGUUUAUGGUACAGUUAGUUAUUUUAUACCUUAAAAACCAACAUACUUACCAUUUCUAUUGUUUAAAAAUUACUGUCCAUUUUUUUAAAAAUUUAAAGAAUGUAGUAUUUUCUGAGGACUGGUAUGGUACAAAAAUGUAAUCAAAAUUUUCAGAUACUACAUUUUUAAAAAGUGAGGAUGGGGAAAAUAUGUAUCAGCAUGACCCUGAUGUAGAAAAAUAAAGUCUGCAAUUGAACCUUGGCAAAAUACAUUACAUAAUUAUUUCUGAUAAGGAUAAAUAUUAGCUGUCAUUUAACUGUCGUGAAGAAUGAAAAAGUGAUACAUUUGGGCUUUUUAGAUCAUUUGUAACUAAAUUUGUACAGAAAUUCUCCUGUGAAAUUAAGUAAACCAUUUUCCAGAUCUUGACUGCAUUGCUGAGAUUUUGCAGUUGAAAAAUAAUUUCAAAUUUUUCAGGUUUUUUGUAUAUUUAUUUUUUUCUAACAAAUAUAUUUAACUAUAAAAUUAAAAUUCAGUAGUUAAACUCUUCAUAAUGCAGAAAUGGAUGGCUUGAUUGUAUAGAAAAAUGAGUCUUUCAGUUACACCAUUCUUGAAAAUAAUAGUGUAUGUUUGAAAUUUGUCAUUAAUUAGUUGCUUUUGAAGGCAAUCUAUUUGAAAUAUGUAAUUUCCUGAUGUUAUCUGCAUUGUGUUAAGAAAAAAAUAAUAGGCUAUAAAAUCAAUUUUUGUAAAAAAAAUGUACAGUUUUAAGUUGUGUACAGAAAAAGGAAGAGCGUACACAGUCUUAGAGUGGAAUAUACCUCUAGUACAGUGUAUGUGUUAAUUCCAACUCAAGCAAAGAAAUGAGUAUUUACCAUCUUUCCUAUAACAUGUAAAUGUAUUAUUCCUGUUCUACAGACACUGUAUAUUUAUGACCUUAUUUGGACAUUAUUAGACACUGGUUUCUUAGUAAAGCACAGUAACUUGGAUCAGAUUCUUUGUAACCGAAACACUUAAACAUGUAUUAGUAAUACCAAUAUAUUUAGAUUUUAUAUUUUUAUAAUUUAGCUUCUAUGCAUUACAGAAGUUGAAUUAAGAAAUUUAAGUCAUCACCAUAUUUUUGUUUUCUUUACCACUUGGGAAAAUAAUCCUCUUUGAGGCAGUAACACUAUGUAUGUACUGUUAAUAGGCCAGAAAGAAAUAUUGGCAGUUGUCUUAGGUAAGCAAUAAAAACAUCUCCAAUUUACUGAAAGUUCAGAAAUAUAACUCUUACAUGCAUGGAAAGUGUAAACCAAUUUAGGUAUUUCUAAGUACCCAACCCUAGUAUUCUCUCCCUCAACUCCAACAUUCUCAAGUCCCAGAUGAAAAGUUUCAGUGGAGCAUUAGUUUAAAUAUUUAGUCUAAUCAGAGACUCACAGCCCUGGGCAAUAGAUACAUAGCUUUUUAAAAUUUUAUCCUUUGUGACCUGCUAUAGUGGCAUUGGACUAUUUUCUGCAUGUAUUAUAAACUAAAGAUUGGCCUUAUUUCAAUUGUUUUUAUUGCACAACUUCACUACAAAUUUAAAGACUGCUGGCAUUAUUAUAAAACUGUCUUCCUCCAAUCCAAGUAAAUAAGUAUGUGGAAUAUUUGUGAGCUGGAUUAGGUAACAUCUGAGACUUGGGAUUGACUAAAUUUAGUUAUCACUUGGAAAUGAAUUACAUAAGAUACAGUAAUCAGAGAAAAUAUCUUUAUGCAGCAUGUAUGUUAACAUCUAGAACUGUCCCUCAUCUGCAGUGCAGUAGAGGAAUCAGACAUUUUAAGAAAUGUAUUCAAAUAUUUUUAUCUUAUAUGUUAGCAGCAUUUACAUGUUUUCAGAUAUGAUUUGUAAUAUAAAUUAAUUUCUCCAGUUAACAAUGUUUACUUCAAUUCUGACAUUCCAUUUUAUACAUAUAUACCUACUGUAUAUCUCUCUCAAAUGUCAGCUAGAAGCAACUUUUUCAGUUUUCUAUCUAAUGAAAACGGAUAUAUUCUGAAUGUUUUUGUUACCUGAAAUUUAUUUUUGAGUAGGUUGAAAGGACCAAGAUACUUGAGUGAUUAAAGGACUGUAAGUGUUCUGCUUAUAUGCAGGAGUUACAUGAUUUUAAAAGUCAUAAUAGGGGAAGUAGUUUUAUCAUCUGAUUACUCCUAUUAACCUAAAAAGUAUUUCUAACAUAACAGAUUGAGCAGUGGUUUUGUUACACUUAGGCAAGAAUUUAUUUUCCCAUUAAAAUUUGAAAAAUACACUUUUCUUUGCUUCUACCCUUGCAGUUUCCCUUAGUUCCCCUAAUUUCCAAGUGAUCUGAACUAAAAUUAAUAUUACAUUUACUAAGAAACUAUUUUUGUUAAUUAUACUGAGCAAAGUUUGCUCCAAAUGAAAAGUCAUUACGAACUAUGUAUAGUACCCAAGAAAAGGUCAAAUUGAGUCAGAAGACUGUAAGUACCACUUUUGGCGCUCCAGAGAUAAACCUUGUACACACUGCAGUAGAACAGUGAGUAGAAAAUAUGAGCUAUAAAUAGAUAUUAUUUUUAGUUUUGAUAGCUCUGUGUUGAAAUACUUUUUUAAUGCAGAUAAAAAUUAUCAGGAAAUUAACCUUAUGGCACAGACCAAAUACUUAGUGCAUGGCUGAGUUUCUACAAUUCAAGGAGCCAAGAAAAUAGGUUCAAGAUGGAAUAUAGUACAUGCAUAUAAGGCAGAUGCACACAUGCUGGUUACUUUAAGAUUGUGUGUGUUGAUUAGUCACAAUGAUAGACUAUAACAUGAGACAAUACAAAGUUACAUUUUUGGACCAUAUUAAAACUGCAAGAAGACAGGGGUCUUACUGAAGAUCUUUUAGAAAACUUAAAUCCUGUCACAGGAUAUUUAGACAUGUGUAGAAUGUAGCUCAAUUUUUAAAAAGUAACUGACCUAGAGGGUGAAAGUUGAAACUGACACAUUUUCAAAUUAAGAUUAUGCUUAUUUUGUACAGAAAACAAUGUUUAAACACAAGCAGAUCUGUUGUAUGUAAUAAGUAACACAGAGUUUUAAAACAAAUUAAUUAUUUAGCUUUAUUGAAGUUUGUUUUUUUCCUUCCGAACCUGGAGUAUCAUAUUAUAAACAGCAGUUUCACACCAGAAUAGCAGUGCCCUUUCUUUUUGUACAUACUGAUUGGACCUUUCUUUACUGUUACGUGGACACUUUCUAUGUUAGUUUUGAUGCAUAAUUCUUUGAAUCCUUUUAUACAAACUAGAAUGUAUGUGUAAGAAUACCUGUCCCUGCAAUGUAGUAACUACAAACUUAUUUUUAAAUAAAUAGAAAACUUGUUUUUCUAAGCUAUUUUGUAGAGCCUCAUGAUUUAUUAUUUGCUUUUUAAAGUUUUUUGGCAUCACAUAAAGCACUUAGUACAUAAUCUCAACAAGCUGCUUACCAAAGUGGUCAUAUGGCAGAUACCAUUAUGUAAAUGCUGGUUCAUUAGAGUUUCCAGUGCCCUGUGUGUUUUGCAAAGUGUGAAAACUGUCAGUUAAAAGAUAUUUGGGUGCCGAAAUGUAAUUUAAUUCCAAAACAACUGAAGGUCAAAAACUUAUAUGCCUUUUUAUGUGUACAUUUAAUAAAACAAUUUUAUUGAUUUCUUACCGUAAGUUACUGUGAUGAGUGAUAAAUACUUCACUAUUCAGAUACUUUCGUAAGAGAUACAUUUCAGUGGAACACUUUGCAUAAAUAUUUUCUCAAAAAUGUGCAAUUUCUGGGAAAAAAGGAAUGAUGGAAAGAAGGUUAUUGCAGUUUUCCUAGAAAUUUUGUCAGAUUGGCAUGCAUUUUUAUUGACUAAGAAUCCCAAUUUUAGCAUGAAGACCAUUAGAUAUGAAUACAUAAGGCCAUAACAUUUCAAAUUAAGCACAUGGAGUGAUUUGUAAUUUUGUGUUAAUUUCUCCCUAAGAUGUUUUGUUAAAAUGAUUUUGUAUAUAAUAAAUUUCUAAGUUGAGGAAGGAAGGUAAAAAAAAUUCCUGAUAACCUUUUCUUUAUGAAGUCUGCUAAUAACAAUACCUAGUAUAUACUUAGAAGAACCAGCCAAGAAAAAUUACCUUUCAGCAACCACUCUUUACUUAUUUCUCUUUUGUAAUAAUACCAAUUUUAUGACCCAGGAUUCCCCAGUAUUUAACGGAAGUAAGAUUAAAGACCAAAGCACAAAACCUCUGUUCCUUGCAAUAUAGUACUUCGUGUUUGUAAUCAAUGUGUGGUAAAUUUAACACAUUUACCACUUACUGAUUAGUCUUUGGGAAAAGAAUGGUGGAAGUCAUUCAAUGAAAUACCUUUCUACCUAAUUGGUUAGACAUACUGGCAGCACAGUGUAAUGAACUGGCCUGGAGUUGGGAAAUGGGAAUUUGACCUUCAUUCCUGACAGGAAGUAGAGGAACCCCAGCAAAGUCGUAUCUCAGAGCUUCAUUUUCCUCAUCUGUAAAGUUUUAAAGGUUGAUUAAAUUAUCUGUGAGGUCUAAUUCUGUUCAAAUAGCCAGUGGUGAUAAUCUCAUUUGUAUACUGUCCUCUGUAUUCAUGGCUCAACUUUGGCUUUUAUAUUUAGUCCCUAAAUAGAAUACAUCAUUUAAUGUGUAGCUUCCAGACAAGCUGUGUCUUGCGGCCAUGACCUGAUUGUUGUUAAGUGUGAGGUUUUCUGAACCCUUAGCAGAAGGACUUUUAAUGUUUUUACAACACACUAUUGUAUUGCUAUAAAUUGUGAAUUGCUUUAAAAGUACAUGUUUACUAAUAAAAAGAAGUACAGGCACACUUUA